AGAGAGCGCCGGCCGCUGGGCUGGCCUGAGAGCGCAGCGCGCCGGCCGCUACCAGCCGCGCCGGAGCCCCUGCGCCCUGCGGCCCGCUCCCCGGGGACCGGGCCGGCGCCAUGGACCGAGGCCAGGGAUCUUGCAACUCAGAUGGUCCAGGACCACCAGCAUCAGCUGCAGCUUGGUGCGGAUCAGAAAUGCAGAAUCUCGGAUCCCACCGCACACCUCCUGAAUCAGAAUUUGCAUUUUGACAAGAUCCCCAGUGCUGGAGCAGCUGCUCCCAGAGCUCACCGGGCUGCUCAGCCUCCUGGACCACGAGUACCUCAGCGAUACCACCCUGGAAAAGAAGAUGGCCGUGGCCUCCAUCCUGCAGAGCCUGCAGCCCCUUCCAGCAAAGGAGGUCUCCUACCUGUAUGUGAACACAGCAGACCUCCACUCGGGGCCCAGCUUCGUGGAAUCCCUCUUUGAAGAAUUUGACUGUGACCUGAGUGACCUUCGGGACAUGCCAGAGGAUGAUGGGGAGCCCAGCAAAGGAGCCAGCCCUGAGCUAGCCAAGAGCCCACGCCUGAGAAACGCGGCCGACCUGCCUCCACCGCUCCCCAACAAGCCUCCCCCUGAGGACUACUAUGAAGAGGCCCUUCCUCUGGGACCCGGCAAGUCGCCUGAGUACAUCAGCUCCCACAAUGGCUGCAGCCCCUCACACUCGAUUGUGGAUGGCUACUAUGAGGACGCAGACAGCAGCUACCCUGCAACCAGGGUGAACGGCGAGCUUAAGAGCUCCUAUAAUGACUCUGACGCAAUGAGCAGCUCCUAUGAGUCCUACGAUGAAGAGGAGGAGGAAGGGAAGAGCCCGCAGCCCCGACACCAGUGGCCCUCAGAGGAGGCCUCCAUGCACCUGGUGAGGGAAUGCAGGAUAUGUGCCUUCCUGCUGCGGAAAAAGCGUUUCGGGCAGUGGGCCAAGCAGCUGACGGUCAUCAGGGAGGACCAGCUCCUGUGUUACAAAAGCUCCAAGGAUCGGCAGCCACAUCUGAGGUUGGCACUGGAUACCUGCAGCAUCAUCUACGUGCCCAAGGACAGCCGGCACAAGAGGCACGAGCUGCGUUUCACCCAGGGGGCUACCGAGGUCUUGGUGCUGGCACUGCAGAGCCGAGAGCAGGCCGAGGAGUGGCUGAAGGUCAUCCGAGAAGUGAGCAAGCCAGUUGGGGGAGCUGAGGGAGUGGAGGUCCCCAGAUCCCCAGUCCUCCUGUGCAAGUUGGACCUGGACAAGAGGCUGUCCCAAGAGAAGCAGACCUCAGAUUCUGACAGCGUGGGUGUGGGUGACAACUGUUCUACCCUUGGCCGCCGGGAGACCUGUGAUCACGGCAAAGGGAAGAAGAGCAGCCUGGCAGAACUGAAGGGCUCAAUGAGCAGGGCUGCGGGCCGCAAGAUCACCCGUAUCAUUGGCUUCUCCAAGAAGAAGACACUGGCCGAUGACCUGCAGACGUCCUCCACCGAGGAGGAGGUUCCCUGCUGUGGCUACCUGAACGUGCUGGUGAACCAGGGCUGGAAGGAACGCUGGUGCCGCCUGAAGUGCAACACUCUGUAUUUCCACAAGGAUCACAUGGACCUGCGAACCCAUGUGAACGCCAUCGCCCUGCAAGGCUGUGAGGUGGCCCCGGGCUUUGGGCCCCGACACCCAUUUGCCUUCAGGAUCCUGCGCAACCGGCAGGAGGUGGCCAUCUUGGAGGCAAGCUGUUCAGAGGACAUGGGUCGCUGGCUCGGGCUGCUGCUGGUGGAGAUGGGCUCCAGAGUCACUCCGGAGGCGCUGCACUAUGACUACGUGGAUGUGGAGACCUUAACCAGCAUCGUCAGUGCUGGGCGCAACUCCUUCCUAUAUGCAAGAUCCUGCCAGAAUCAGUGGCCUGAGCCCCGAGUCUAUGAUGAUGUUCCUUAUGAAAAGAUGCAGGACGAGGAGCCCGAGCGCCCCACAGGGGCCCAGGUGAAGCGUCACGCCUCCUCCUGCAGUGAGAAGUCCCAUCGUGUGGACCCGCAGGUCAAAGUCAAACGCCACGCCUCCAGUGCCAAUCAAUACAAGUAUGGCAAGAACCGAGCCGAGGAGGAUGCCCGGAGGUACUUGGUAGAAAAAGAGAAGCUGGAGAAAGAGAAAGAGACGAUUCGGACAGAGCUGAUAGCACUGAGACAGGAGAAGAGGGAACUGAAGGAAGCCAUUCGGAGCAGCCCAGGAGCAAAAUUAAAGGCUCUGGAAGAAGCCGUGGCCACCCUGGAAGCUCAGUGUCGGGCAAAGGAGGAGCGCCGGAUUGACCUGGAGCUGAAGCUGGUGGCUGUGAAGGAGCGCUUGCAGCAGUCCCUGGCAGGAGGGCCAGCCCUGGGGCUCUCCGUGAGCAGCAAGCCCAAGAGUGGGGAAACUGCAAAUAAACCCCAGAACAGCGUUCCAGAGCAACCUCUCCCUGUCAACUGUGUUUCUGAGCUGAGGAAGAGGAGCCCAUCCAUCGUAGCCUCCAACCAAGGAAGGGUGCUACAGAAAGCCAAGGAAUGGGAAAUGAAGAAGACCUAGGAAGAGGAUGAGGAUUUCAUUCCAAAGGAAAUACCAGCUUGUCCACCUGAGGAAGAAAUGCUUUUUUCACAAGGAGACACCAAGAGAAGACUAGGAAGUAGCCCUCGUUCUCCAGGGCACCCAAAAUACCAGCCUUUAUUGUCUGCAUGAUUUUAGGGGAUAUGGGGAGGGAACAAGUAGAAGGGAAGAGGGAAAUGGAGAGCAUCCUUAUGACUUUACAAAGGGUGGAAAUGAGGAUGGAGGGAUACAGAAGUCUGCACAGCUGUAAAGGUUUUAUAGAUGUCUUUGCCUUCCCUUCUGAGGAAGGGAAGAAGUAAUGAAAGCACAUGUGAAUAACCCCUUCCAUCCCAUUCACAGCAUCGCACUCCCAGUCCUUAAGGCAAAGGGAGGCAGUGCUGAAGCAUUGGUGGUGCAGUGUAAAGAGACAAGACCUGAUCAUCUGAUCACACUUGUGCCAACUUGAUUCAUAUUGGGCAUUACUAACAACCCCUGGUCAAGGUAAAUAGGUUGAACAAUCAAUAACAUUAUCCCUGCCUGCAUACAUGUGAACAAAAGCUAUAGAGGACAUGCAAAUUCUACAGUCAUUCCUCAUAUGCUUUAGACAGAGUGCAGCUACUGGAAUCUUCCAGAUUUCAGUGUUUUAAAAUCAGAGCUCUGAAUACACAAAAGGAAAGAGAAAUGGAGCAGCUGACAUAUUUUAAGCUCACAGUGAUACUCAGUGACAGGAGCACAGAGCUCUAAUGUCCACAGGAUGUUGUAGGGUAGGGUCUCUCAGUAAAUCAAGUCCCUUACCUAUGUUCUGACACUGAGGCUCUUGGAGCUAUGGGUUAGAAAUCCAGGAGGCAAUAUGUCUUUAUUCUAAUGAAGUCCUCAUCUUGCACUCAGAGGCCCACUAGUUUGCCCUUCUAUAUAUUAAGUAAAACCAAGAGAAAUUAAGAGGAUGAUGGCUUCUUUCUGUCACAUGGGUGCUAAACCUUUUACAAACACUUGAUACUUCUAUAGAGGGACCAAGGACCUCAAGUCCUGGGCAGUCUCCUUACUGUGCUACUCACUACUGUCUCAACACUGUAGUGAGUCUGUCUUUAACACAUUUCCUUCCAAUAAAGAUAAAACCACUUAACUCUUAAGUGCCAGUGCUUAGCUCAAGAGGAAAGAAGGAAAAUCCCAGAAUAACCGUGGCCACUUUGCUAUAGGGGUUACAUAUUUUAACCCACCUAAGGUUUUACAGACUUUAGCCUCACUCAAACUUUAUCACCCUCUGAGGUAGCUGGAGACCACAGCAGGAAAAAUAACCUGACCAGUAAUCACCCACUGAUUAGUGGCAGAGCGUAGGACUUAGGGGUUAUAAGCCCAGAUCCAGAUAGGGCUAGGUUUGAGCCAUGCCUCUAAUGACCAGCUGGGUGACCUUGGGAAAGUCACUUGAUUGCUCUGAUUCUUGUUUUCCUUAUCUGUGAAAUGGGACUAACAAUUGUUACUUUUCUCCCAAGAUUGUUGGGAAGAUUUAAUAAGAUAAUAUAUAGUAGGCAUCUUGCAUAGUGUCUGAGAAAUAAGAAAUGCUCAGUCAAUAGUGGCUCUCAUUAGCCAGGCAUGGUGGUACUCGCCUGUAGUCCCAGCUACUCAGGAGGCUGAGGCAGGAGGACCGCUUGAGCCCAGGAGUUUGAGACUGUAGUGCACUAUGAUCACGCCUGUGAAUUGCCACUGCACUCCAGCCUAAGCAAAUAGCAAGACCCCAUCUAUUAAAAAAAAAAAGUGGCUAUUAUUAGCUAUAUCAGAAAUGUCUGACUCACAAGCCUGUGUUCUUUCCACUGAAGAGGAAAUUACUUUUCAGUGUUCUUUUUUAAAACGUGGAUCCUGAAAUGUCACCUAACUCUCCAACUAUGUCUUCAGUGUCUGUCAUACUCUUUCUUAUGCAGUUAUUUUGGGGUUAAGUGUCUUUUCUCACCAACAGAUGAACUCUCAGAGGAGUGGCUGGGGGUAAUUAAUAAUUAACAUUUAUCAAGCACUCACCAUAUGUCAGGCACUGUGUCAGCCAUGGCCAGCUUCACAGGCAUGCAACCUGUGCAGUCACACAGGGCCCCAUGCUUAGAAGGGCCCUGUUCUUGGUUUAAUGCUCUACUAUUGCCUUCUUAAUCAUAUUUGAACAAGGAGUUCUGCUUUUCCUUUUGCCCUUUAAAUUAGAUAGCCAGUCCUGGUGCUAACUAACCACUUUUCUAGGUAUUAUCCCUUUAGUUUUCACUGAAACCCUGAGAUAAGUUAUAUUGCCCUAGUUUUCACAGUUCAGGAAAUGGAAGCUCACAGAGGUCAGGUAACUUGUCCAAGCUCCCAUAGUUCUUAUAUUUACAUGCUGGUGGAGCCAGCAUGUGAAUAUAAGAAGUCUGACCCUAGAGCCUUAUUCUUAAUUUUAAAGCUCUAUGUCAUCCAUAUAUCUCCCUCCCCUUGUACUGCAACAUUCAGAAGCACACUAGCACUUAAUAAAUAGACGAAUGAAUGCAUGGAUGCAAGCAGCAACCUGGUGAACGUUAGGCAGCUAGGAGAAAUGUAAGCAAAAUGGCUAAGGCACAGAUGCCACUUGUUCUUGGUUGUUAAAAUGCCUUGUUUAGGCCAGGUAUGGUGGCUCAUGCCUGUAAUCCCAGCACUUUGGGAGGCCGAAGCGGGUGGAUCACUUGAGGUCAGGAGUUCAAGACCAGCCUGGCCAACAUGGCAAAACCCCAUCUCUAUCAAAAAUACAAAAGUUAGCUGGGCACGGUGGCACAUGCCGGUAGUCCCAGCUACUUGGGAGGCUGAGGGAGGAGAAUCACUUGAACCCGGGAGGUGGAGGUUGCAGUGAGCCGAGAUCGCACCACUGCACUCCAGCCUGGGCAAUAGCAAGACUCCAUCUCAAAAAAAAAAAAAUGCCUUAUUUGGUUGUGUUUUUUCAAAGUGUAAGCCACAGGUCUAAGCCCAACACUGCCAAGUGUUCAGUCUGUCAGAAUUCUACUGUCACUGUUUCCUUAUUGCGGGAUCUUGCAUAGGUUUACCAACCUUUCUGAGCCUCAAUUUUCUCAUAUGUAAAAGAGAAUCAUAAUACCUCCCUAAACCAUAUCACCCUUUUCAUAAGGCCAAAAAGAAAAUAUAAGUUAUUGGUCAUGACACAUUUGAGUUGGACCUCGGAUUAGAUAAAAAGAUGAAAAUACUCCAGCUCUGUCCUCAUGGAACUCAGAGACAAGCAGGAAAGAAAAUGUGACCCAAAUAACUACAGUACAAAUAACCCAUGUUAUGACAAGAUUCAGAGUGCUCAAGGAACACUUCCCAUUCCCUUAAAAAAAAAAAUUAAGGGACUAUCCAGUAACUAAGCUGGCAACUCCAAGUGCCCUGGACCCCAGUCACCAAUCCAUCCUCUCAGUCUGUCAGCUUUCCAUCCUAAAUCUCUAAAAUUCAUCCAUAUCUUCCUAUCUUCACUGACACUAUCCAACUUAAUUAAGUCAUUCAACAAAUACUUGAGUACCUACUAUACUAGAUGUCAGAAAUCAGUGGUGAACAAGACAGACACCUCAUGAAGCUCACAUUCUAGUUGGAGGAAAAAACCUUAACAAGGAAGCAAAAGAAAUAAAAUACUAAGAAACUAAAA